CAGGCUGAGCGUUGGAAGCCAUUUUGGCUGCAACCUACCUGAAGCGAUGUCUGCCUUUGGUCACGACGAGGCCUGGAUGGAGGCCGGAGGCUUUGGUCUGGAGGCUGCCGAAAGAACGGAAUACCAGUCUCUGUGCAAAUCUAAACUCUUAUUCCUGGGAGAGCAGAGCGUAGGGAAGACAUCCAUCAUCAGCCGCUUCAUGUACAACAGCUUCGGCUGCGCCUGCCAGGCAACUGUUGGAAUUGACUUCUUGUCUAAGACCAUGUACUUGGAGGACCAAAUAGUUCAGCUGCAGCUAUGGGACACAGCUGGCCAGGAGCGCUUUCACAGCCUAAUUCCUAGCUACAUUCGUGAUUCAACUAUUGCAGUGGUUGUCUAUGACAUUACAAACAUCAAUUCUUUUAAGGAGACAGAUAAGUGGGUAGAACACGUGCGAGCAGAAAGAGGUGACGAUGUUGUCAUCAUGUUGUUGGGUAACAAGAUUGAUUUGGAUAACAAAAGACAAGUCACUGCAGAACAGGGUGAAGAAAAAUCCAGAAACCUCAAUGUGAUGUUUAUUGAGACCAGUGCCAAAACCGGUUACAACGUGAAAAAGCUGUUCCGGCGUGUGGCUUCUGCCCUUCUUUCCACAAGGACUUCACCUCCACCAAAAGAGGGGAGUAUCCUUUUUCCUAGCUUUGCUGGGGUAGGGAGUAUACAAGUAGAGAAGGUAAGUUUCCUUGCUGAGUUGAUGCCUGAGUGGUACCUAAGGGGAAAAUGGGACUAACUUUAGCCCAAAGUAGUUCCUUCGUUUGCCUUUAGGUGAGAGGGAUUGUAAGAUCAGAAUUCCUCUUCUACAUCUCCUAGAAGCUGACCUUGGGUGUUAAGAUUUGACUCCAGUCACCUCACUGUAUUAGCUUCCUUGACACACACUUCAGCGGUUGAAAUCGAACUGGAAUCCUUCGAGGAGUCAGGCAACAGAAGCUAUUGUUGACAGCUUAGGCUUUCUCUGCCUCAUUUGAUGGAUUUCUUACAUUUGGGCUUGCCAUACCAGUUCUCCUCCCCACCUCGUUUUAUGAUACAUGGCCACUUACUCUCUUCCAAUUCCUAGGCUUGGGGUAAAAACAGAACCCCUGAAAGUGCUAUCAUUUUUUCCUGACCGCAUCUCACAGCUACUGGGUGGAAGCUUCUUGCAGCACCUGGGAAUUCUACCUUACCUUCUCCGACAGCUAAAAGACAUCUGUAGAGAAUACAGUUCUACAGCAGCUGACAUACUUCAAAGGCCAAUACAAUUCAUUCUCCACUGUUUGUUGUUGUUUACCUACACCCUCAAUAAAUGGUUCUUUAACCUAA